GCAGUGCGGCGCCUAGAGGGAAAGCGAGAGGGAGACGGACGUUGAGAGAACGAGGAGGAAGGAGAGAAAAUGGCGUCCACGGAUUACAGUACCUAUAGCCAAGCUGCAGCGCAGCAGGGCUACAGUGCUUACACCGCCCAGCCCACUCAAGGAUAUGCACAGACCACCCAGCAGGCAUAUGGGCAACAAAGCUAUGGAACCUAUGGACAGCCCACUGAUGUCAGCUAUACCCAGGCUCAGACCACUGCAACCUAUGGGCAGACCGCCUAUGCAACUUCUUAUGGACAGCCUCCCACUGGUUAUACUACUCCAACUGCCCCCCAGGCAUACAGCCAGCCUGUCCAGGGGUAUGGCACUGGUGCUUAUGAUACCACCACUGCUACAGUCACCACCACCCAGGCCUCCUAUGCAGCUCAGUCUGCAUAUGGCACUCAGCCUGCUUAUCCAGCCUAUGGGCAGCAGCCAGCAGCCACUGCACCUACAAGACCGCAGGAUGGAAACAAGCCCACUGAGACUAGUCAACCUCAAUCUAGCACAGGGGGUUACAACCAGCCCAGCCUAGGAUAUGGACAGAGUAACUACAGUUAUCCCCAGGUACCUGGGAGCUACCCCAUGCAGCCAGUCACUGCACCUCCAUCCUACCCUCCUACCAGCUAUUCCUCUACACAGCCGACUAGUUAUGAUCAGAGCAGUUACUCUCAGCAGAACACCUAUGGGCAACCGAGCAGCUAUGGACAGCAGAGUAGCUAUGGUCAACAAAGCAGCUAUGGGCAGCAGCCUCCCACUAGUUACCCACCCCAAACUGGAUCCUACAGCCAAGCUCCAAGUCAAUAUAGCCAACAGAGCAGCAGCUACGGGCAGCAGAGUUCAUUCCGACAGGACCACCCCAGUAGCAUGGGUGUUUAUGGGCAGGAGUCUGGAGGAUUUUCCGGACCAGGAGAGAACCGGAGCAUGAGUGGCCCUGAUAACCGGGGCAGGGGAAGAGGGGGAUUUGAUCGUGGAGGCAUGAGCAGAGGUGGGCGGGGAGGAGGACGCGGUGGAAUGGGCAGCGCUGGAGAGCGAGGUGGCUUCAAUAAGCCUGGUGGACCCAUGGAUGAAGGACCAGAUCUUGAUCUAGGCCCACCUGUAGAUCCAGAUGAAGACUCUGACAACAGUGCAAUUUAUGUACAAGGAUUAAAUGACAGUGUGACUCUAGAUGAUCUGGCAGACUUCUUUAAGCAGUGUGGGGUUGUUAAGAUGAACAAGAGAACUGGGCAACCCAUGAUCCACAUCUACCUGGACAAGGAAACAGGAAAGCCCAAAGGCGAUGCCACAGUGUCCUAUGAAGACCCACCCACUGCCAAGGCUGCCGUGGAAUGGUUUGAUGGGAAAGAUUUUCAAGGGAGCAAACUUAAAGUCUCCCUUGCUCGGAAGAAGCCUCCAAUGAACAGUAUGCGGGGUGGUCUGCCACCCCGUGAGGGCAGAGGCAUGCCACCACCACUCCGUGGAGGUCCAGGAGGCCCAGGAGGUCCUGGGGGACCCAUGGGUCGCAUGGGAGGCCGUGGAGGAGAUAGAGGAGGCUUCCCUCCAAGAGGACCCCGGGGUUCCCGAGGGAACCCCUCUGGAGGAGGAAACGUCCAGCACCGAGCUGGAGACUGGCAGUGUCCCAAUCCUUCAAUUGGUGAUUUCUGCUGUGAUGUAAUUGUAUGCAGGGGUUGUGGAAACCAGAACUUCGCCUGGAGAACAGAGUGCAACCAGUGUAAGGCCCCAAAGCCUGAAGGCUUCCUCCCGCCACCCUUUCCGCCCCCGGGUGGUGAUCGUGGCAGAGGUGGCCCUGGUGGCAUGCGGGGAGGAAGAGGUGGCCUCAUGGAUCGUGGUGGUCCCGGUGGAAUGUUCAGAGGUGGCCGUGGUGGAGACAGAGGUGGCUUCCGUGGUGGCCGGGGCAUGGACCGAGGUGGCUUUGGUGGAGGAAGACGAGGUGGCCCUGGGGGGCCCCCUGGACCUUUGAUGGAACAGAUGGGAGGAAGAAGAGGAGGACGUGGAGGACCUGGAAAAAUGGAUAAAGGCGAGCACCGUCAGGAGCGCAGAGAUCGGCCCUACUAGAUGCAGAGACCCCGCAGAGCUGCAUUGACUACCAGAUUUAUUUUUUAAACCAGAAAAUGUUUUAAAUUUAUAAUUCCAUAUUUAUAAUGUUGGCCACAACAUUAUGAUUAUUCCUUGUCUGUACUUUAGUAUUUUUCACCAUUUGUGAAGAAACAUUAAAACAAGUUAAAUGGUAGUGUGCGGAGUUUUUUUUUCUUCCUUCUUUUAAAAAUGGUUGUUUAAGACUUUAACAAUGGGAACCCCUUGUGAGCAUGCUCAGUAUCAUUGUGGAGAACCAAGAGGGCCUCUUAACUGUAACAAUGUUCAUGGUUGUGAUGUUUUUUUUUUUUUUUUAAAUAAAAUUCCAAAUGUUUAUAAAGA